GGGGCCGCGUAGGGCCCACUGGCCAGGGAGGGCGCCGCGCGGAGGCGCGGGGCGUGUCUCCUGUCAAAAGCCAUGCUCGGCAGGUCUGGGUACCGGGCGCUGCCCCUGGGUGAUUUUGACCGCUUCCAGCAGUCGAGCUUCGGCUUUCUGGGCUCGCAGAAGGGCUGCUUGUCCCCGGAGCGGGGCGGCGUGGGGACAGGGGCCGAUGUACCCCAGAGCUGGCCCUCCUGCCUCUGUCAUGGCCUCAUCAGUUUCCUGGGGUUCUUGCUGCUGUUGGUCACCUUCCCCAUUUCUGGCUGGUUUGCCCUGAAGAUUGUGCCCACCUACGAGCGGAUGAUUGUGUUCCGCCUGGGCCGGAUCCGCACCCCCCAGGGACCUGGCAUGGUUCUGCUCUUGCCCUUCAUUGACUCCUUUCAGAGGGUGGAUCUGAGGACACGAGCCUUCAACGUCCCUCCCUGCAAGGUGAGGGGCUUCUCAGCUGCCUUGACAGAGGAACUGGGGGCCUGUCCAGAAUGUACUGUGGUGCCAGGACCUCAGCCUGUGAGUCACCAUCUGAGGGGGGAAGGGGGAAGAAGAGACCAGAAAAUUGAUGGAAGCUAGGAGGACAUCCUUGCUUCAUACACCUAACCCUACAUACUUGGUGACACCAUUUGCCCUUGAGGAGCUAGCUGCCAAGCAGGUGGUUCAAGCUGGGUGGCCCCAGUGGGCCUGACCUCCCUGCACCCCCAGCCCCUUGAGUGUCUCUCUCUCAUGGCCUCCCCCAACAGCUGGCCUCUAAGGACGGGGCUGUGCUGUCCGUGGGAGCCGAUGUCCAGUUUCGCAUCUGGGACCCGGUGCUGUCGGUGAUGACUGUGAAAGACCUGAACACAGCCACACGCAUGACAGCCCAGAACGCCAUGACCAAGGCCCUGCUCAAGAGGCCGCUGCGGGAGAUCCAGAUGGAGAAGCUCAAGAUCAGCGACCAGCUUCUGCUGGAGAUCAACGAUGUGACCAGGGCCUGGGGGCUGGAGGUAGACCGCGUGGAGCUGGCAGUGGAGGCCGUGCUCCAGCCGCCCCAGGACAGCCCAGCUGGGCCCAACCUGGACAGCACCCUCCAGCAGCUGGCCCUGCACUUCCUGGGAGGAAGCAUGAACUCAAUGGCAGGAGGUGCCCCGUCCCCGGGGCCAGCAGACACCGUGGAGAUGGUGAGUGAAGUUGAGCCACCUGCCCCUCAAGUUGGUGCCAGGUCCAGUCCGAAGCAGCCUCUGGCGGAGGGGCUACUGACUGCUCUACAGCCCUUCCUGUCUGAGGCCCUGGUCAGCCAAGUCGGGGCCUGCUACCAGUUCAAUGUCGUCCUGCCCAGCGGCACCCAAAGCGCCUACUUCCUGGACCUCACUACAGGACGAGGAAGAGUGGGACACGGGGUGCCUGAUGGCAUCCCUGAUGUGGUGGUGGAGAUGGCCGAGGCAGACCUGCGGGCCCUGCUAUGCAGAGAGCUGCGGCCCCUGGGGGCCUACAUGAGUGGACGGCUGAAGGUGAAGGGCGACCUGGCUAUGGCCAUGAAGCUGGAGGCUGUCCUCAGGGCCUUGAAGUAGCAGCCUUGGCUGACUUUCCAGAGCCCAGUCCCAAGCCUGGCACCAAGCCUGAGGGGCCUCUUGGAGGAGGAGGUGUUCAUCUGCACCACAGAGAGUUGAGGCCCUAACAAAUUUCAGGCCCAGCCAAGAGCCCAUGAAUGGAGGCUGCAGGAGGCUGAGUCCGGCUGCCAUGCACGUCUCCCCUACAGUGGUUCUCUGGACAAGGCUUUGUCCAUCCCGGUCCCCAGCUGAGUGCCCAGCGCUGAGCUGGGUGCACGGUGUGAUUCCAGGAGGAGAGCCAGGCCUGCCCUGCCCUGCUGGCUUCCUGACUGGAGAGACAGGACCCACAGAAACAGCCUGACAGCAGCUGGUUUGGUCCUUGUGUGAGGGACCAAGCAUGUGGCCCAGGCUCUAAGCUCUGCGGGGAUUGGAGAGGGAUGGGGAGGGAAGGGAAGGCAGCUCCAAGAAGAGGUCCCUGUGGCGAAGUUACCUGGGGAUCCUGGCUGGCCCACCUUCCUGGCUGCAGUCCAGGCCCGUGCUGGCGGGAUUGGGCAUGGGAAGGAGCAGGGCCUGCUGCUUCCCUGGCGCUGCUCCCAAAGAUUUCUGACUCAUCUGCCAGCUCUGUCCUGCAUGCCUGGCGAGCUGGGGCCCAGGGCAGCAUGAAGGAGAGCCCUGCGUUCUGUGCUUCUUACCAGAGGUUUGCAAGCCUCAGACAAAUAAAUGUGGUGUUUACAAUGUAUAAAAGAGAAGAAGCCAAGCGGGGCUCCUGGGGGCAUGGGGUGGGCUAGGAGGGUCCACAAGGUCCAUGCUGCCAGCCCAGGCAGGGAUUGACAUCCUGGUGGCUGACACAGACAGACCCUCACAAUAUUUGAAGCUCCUUCUCCUGAGUGUCUCAAAGCCCCUGGAAGCAAGGGUGGGGCUGGGUGGGGAGUUCUGUUCCUCUUUGUAGUGGGAUACAGGUUCACCAGGAAAGGAAGGCAUGAGUGUGCCAGAGUGUCCUGCAAACACUGAGGGGCAGGUGGGGUGGUCAUAUCCCAUUCAAGAGAGGAGUUGGGGCCACCGUCAGCUUCCCCUCCUGGUACACUCUGUCACUGCUUCUCCGCUCGCUGACGGGAAGGAAACAGUCAUUGAGGUCUGGCCCCAGGCCCAGCCCAGCCCUGCUUUCUGCUCCAGUACUCUCGCCCAAACCCCAGGGGCCCCAGAGAAGGGGGCCUCUGACUUCUUGAGUCCUAAGAAAGGAAUCUUACUCCUUGGAGAGACUUCUGGGAAAAACAAAACCACAAAAAUCAAAGCCUCCCCUUAAGAACAGCCCCCAGCCUGUCCUGUGGCACCGCAACUUCCCUCUCCCCCAAGGGGUCUCUGCCCUUCCUGGGUGCCUGGCUCUGUCUUGUUUGCUGUCUGUCCCUGCCUUUGCCAGACACUGCCUUGUCCCGCCUCCUGGAGGUCCUCCACAUUGCCUGAGGCACCUCCCUAAAGCCCAGCACAGACCCCUCUGUCACUGCCAUGGCCAUUGAGGUUCAGGUUUCCAGGGCCCCUUCCUAGAGUCCCAGGCUGCUGCACCUGCUGUUGCCCCUUUGCCUACUUGGAGGCCUCUCAUGGGCCCUCCCAGGGCUUUCUAGCUGAGGCUGUCUGUUCCAAAGCCUGCCCUCCAAUCCCCGCAGCCACACUGUGGCCACCCUUUGAGGCCCAGUGAGACUUGUCCUCUGUGCCCUUGCCUGGCUCUCUGCACCCAUUCCACAUUGUGUGUUUCUGCUCCUUGCAUAUAUGGCUGCCCUCCCUGCUGGACUGGGAGCUUCCUGCAUCAGCAUUCACCUGUGGAUUCCUUCCAUUGCUAUUACACAGUAUAUGAAGGGCUGCCCAGGAAACCCCAGGCAUCUUCACCAUGAAAGCUGGCACGGCCCCUUGGCUGGGGUAGGGCUGGAGGGUAGGGAAGACAGGAAAAAUGAGAUCACAACUUAGGGGAAACCCAAACUCUUCUUUGUGAGCAUGGGAAGAUCAACAUAACGUUUAGGGGAAACCGAAACUUUUCUGGAUGUCUGUGUAGGUGGAGAGUAAGGCCUGCCCCUGCCAUGAAUCCCCACCCUGUGGAGGGGAGCUCGAUCCUUGGCCAGCACUCCAGGACUACAGAGGACUGAGCAGACCCUGCAGUCCACAGGGGAGGAAGGACAAGGGCCACCUAAAGGGUCGGUGUGAAGAGGGAGGAGGAGGGUGUGUGUCAAUCAGAGAAGGCUUUCCUGAGGAGGUGAUGUCCUCCACAUCCCAGCUACCAAGUAGGUGGACAAUAAGAAGAGAUGGGGAAAAUCAUUCAGCAGAGGAGAAGUCCCUGCAAGGGCACAGCUGGAAGAGGCAGUCAGGCAACUGGGCUUCGGGGAACUAGAACCUGAAGUACCAGACAGGUUGUGUGCGGGCAUUUGAGGGGCAGGGUAUAGAAAUAGUAACCAUUACUGUGUGCCAAAUAUGUCCUUAUACCGGACUAGACACUUCUUAUUAUAUUUUUCUUCAAGAUAACCUGGUGAAUAAUGAUAAUAGUUUAAGUAUCCUAGUUAAUAUAUUAAUAUAUAAUGUGUUAUUUUGAUGUUAUUGAAAAGUAUUUUAUUUUUUUUUGAAACAAGAGUCUUACUCUGUUGCCCAUGUUAGAGUACAGUACAAUCUCAGCUCACUGCAACCUCUACCUCCCGGAUUCAAGUGAUUCUCCUGCCUCAGACACCUGAGUAGCCAGGAUUAUAGGCGCAUACCACCACACCUGGUUAAUUUUUGUAUUUUUAGUAGAGAUGGGAUUUCACCAUGUUGACCAGGCUGGUCUCGAACUCCUGACCUCAAGUGAUCUGCCUGCCUAGGCCUCCCAAAGUGCUGGGAUUAUAGGUGUGAGCCACCGCACCUGGCCUUAUUUUUAAGCAUUUAAAAAAAAUUUUUUAGACCGUCUUGCUCUAUCACCCAGGCUGGAGUGCAGUGGCAUGAUCAUAGCUCACUGUAGCCUUGAACUCUGGGGCUCAAACGAUCCUCUUGCCUCAGCUUCCUGAGUAGCUGGGACCACAGGUUGUGCCACCACAACCGGCUAAUUUUUAAAAUCUCUUUUGUAGAGAUAAGGAUGUCUCCCCAUGUUGCUCAGGCUGGUCUUGAACUCCUGGGCUCGCAGGAUCCUCCCACCACAGCCUCCCAAAGUGCUGGGAUUACAGGUGUGAGCCACUGUACCCAGCCAAUAUUUAAAUUUUGGUUGGCUAAACAUUUAAAAAGAUAGGAAAGCAUAUUAUGAAAAUUCUCCCUCCACACAUAUUUCCCAUGCCUUCCCCCAUCCCCUGCGAUUAGUUUCUUGGUAAUUCUUCCUGAAGGUUUUGUUUUUUAAAAAAAAAUAUAUGCAAGAAAAUCCAAAUAUGUAUCUUCUGGGUUUUUGUUGUUCCUGUUUUUAUACAAAUGGCAACAUAGAAACACAAUGUUGCCUUUUUCACUUAACAUUACCCACUGAGGAUCUUUCCAUGUUACCACAGACAGCCUUUCCCUGUGCUUUCUUGUACUUACAUAGGAUUCCACAGUAUGGAUGUAUCAUAAAUUAUUCAACCUGUCGUGGACCGAUAGACAUUUUGAUUAUUUCUUGUGUUUUGCUAUUUUAAAUACUUUUGCAAUGAAUAACCUUUAACAUGUGCUAUUUGUGGUAGAGUUUAUCUAUAAGAUAAAAUCCUAGAAGUGGAAUUGCUAAAUCAAAGCAUUUAUAAUUUAGUAAAUAUUGCCAGAAUACCUUCUCUGGGGAUUAUACCAAUUUACACUCCCAUUGUCAGUGGUGUUUUUUUCUCAUAGUCAUGUCAAUACACUGUGUUAUUAAACUUUUGGGUCUUUUGACAUUCUGGAAAGUGAAAAUUUGUAUCUCAGUGUAAUUUUUUUGUUUAUUGUUCAAGUUAUUUUUUUGUUUUUUGUUUGUUUGUUUUGAGACAGGGUCUCACUCUGUCUCCCAGGCUGGAGUGCAGUGCAGUGAUUGUGGCUCACUGCAGCCUCAACCUCCCAGGCUUAAAGGAUCACCAUGCCUGGCUUUUUUUUUUUUUUUUUUUUUGUAGAGACAGGGCCUUCUCAAGCUGGUCUCUAACUCCUGGCCUCAAGUGAUCCUCCCACCUGGCCCUGGCCCGCUAACUGCUAGGAUUACAGGCAUGAGCCAUCUAGCCCAGCCUGUUUAUUGUCCAAUUGUUUAUUGCUUUGUAAGUCUUGGAUUUCUAGCUCCAGCAAAGAACAGGGUUUGGUUUGGUUUGGUUUCUCUUCCCCUAGCAUUUACAUAUUUUUUAAAGGUGUAAUUUACAUACAACAAACACCCUUUUAAAAUGUAUUAUUUGGCUGGCUUGCGCCUCUAAUCCCAGCACUUUGGGAGGCCGAGGCAGGUGGAUCACCUGAGGUCAGGAGUUUGAGACCAGCCUGACCGAUAUGGUGAAACCCCAUCUCUACUAAAAAUACAAAAUUUAGCCAGGCAUGGUGGUACACGGCUGUAGUCCCAGCUACUCGGGAGGCUGAGACAGGAGAAUUGCUUGAACCCAGGAGGUGGAAGUUGCAGUGAGUUGAGAUCAUGCCACUGCACUUUAGCCUGGGCAACAGAGUGAGACUCCAUCUCAAAAUUAAAUAAAUAAAGAUAAAAUAAAAAGUGUCAUCUGAGGUGCUUUGACAAAUGUGAACACCUGAGUAACCACCACCCCCUACAAUCAAAUACAAAACAUUCCCAUCCACUCACAAAGUUCUCCACGUCACUUCCCGUCAGUGCUUGCCACCUCCAGCUUUGAGCAGCCACUGACCUUUCCAUAACCGCUGAUCACAUUUCACUUUUCUAGCAUUUCAUAUGAAUGAAAUGAGUGCACAGUACUCUUCUGUGUCUAGCUUUUUCCCCCUCACUGUAAUGGUUUUGAGAGUAAUACAUGUUAUUCUGUGUAUCUGUAGUUUGUUGUAUUGCCAACACAUUCCAUUGUCUAGAUAGAGGCACAAUGUAUUCAUUCAUCCAUUGAUGAACAUUUGAGUAGUUUUCAGGUUUGGUUAUUAAAUAAAGCUCCUCCAGACAUCUGUG